AAGCAGCGGCCAAUCAAGGCAGGGGAUGGAGGCAAGUGGGGGUCGCGCCUGGAGCGGAGCCUCGGCCUCCGGAGCCGCAGCUGCAGCCCUGUAUUGAGCUGAGAUGGCUCGAGCCUAACAUUCCAUGAUCCAGGAUCGUGACAGAUGUGCACAGGCUGCUGCUGUUGCUGCUGUGGGUAAUUUGGAACCACGAGGCACCCCAGGGCCAGAAGACGAGGCAUUCUGUCUGCCUGGAUGUGUGGGAACUCUCUGCCAACUUGAUUGGUGGAUCUGGGGGGGGAUCCACCCCCACCCCACGAGGAAAGCACAGUUUAUUUUGUGGGUGGGGCUUCAGGUGCCAGCCAGCUGAAGGAUGGCCACCCCUGUGGUCACCAAGACAGCCUGGAAGUUGCAAGAGAUCGUCGCGCAUGCCAGCAACGUGUCCUCACUGGUGCUGGGCAAAGCCUCCGGGCGGCUGCUGGCUACAGGCGGGGAUGACUGCCGCGUCAACCUGUGGUCCAUCAACAAGCCCAACUGCAUCAUGAGCCUGACGGGCCACACAUCCCCAGUGGAGAGCGUCCGCCUCAACACCCCCGAGGAGCUCAUCGUGGCCGGCUCUCAGUCGGGCUCCAUCCGUGUCUGGGACCUGGAAGCUGCCAAAAUUCUUCGCACACUCAUGGGACACAAAGCCAACAUCUGCAGCCUGGAUUUCCACCCGUACGGCGAGUUUGUAGCCUCUGGUUCCCAGGACACAAACAUCAAGCUCUGGGACAUCAGGAGGAAAGGCUGUGUCUUCCGAUACAGGGGGCACAGCCAGGCCGUGCGGUGUCUCCGGUUCAGCCCCGAUGGGAAGUGGUUGGCGUCGGCCGCAGAUGACCACACCGUGAAGCUCUGGGAUCUCACUGCCGGCAAGAUGAUGUCUGAGUUCCCUGGUCACACGGGGCCUGUCAACGUGGUCGAGUUUCACCCCAACGAGUACCUCCUGGCCUCCGGCAGCUCUGACAGGACAAUCCGCUUCUGGGACCUGGAGAAGUUCCAGGUGGUGAGCUGCAUCGAAGGGGAGCCUGGGCCCGUCAGGAGCGUCCUCUUCAACCCAGACGGCUGCUGCCUGUACAGCGGCUGCCAGGACUCACUGCGUGUCUACGGCUGGGAACCUGAGCGGUGCUUUGAUGUGGUCCUCGUCAACUGGGGCAAGGUGGCCGACCUGGCCAUCUGCAAUGACCAGUUGAUAGGUGUGGCCUUCUCCCAGAGCAACGUCUCCUCCUACGUGGUGGAUCUGACGCGUGUCACCAGGACUGGCACGGUGGCCCGGGACCCUGUGCAGGACCACCGGCCCCUGGCACAGCCACUGCCCAACCCCAGCGCCCCCCUCCGGCGCAUCUAUGAGCGGCCCAGCACAACCUGCAGCAAGCCUCAGAGGGUGAAGCAGAACUCAGAGAGCGAGCGCCGCAGCCCCAGCAGCGAGGAUGACCGGGACGAGCGCGAGUCCCGCGCGGAGAUCCAGAACGCCGAGGACUACAACGAGAUCUUCCAGCCCAAGAACAGCAUCAGUCGGACGCCACCCCGGAGAAGUGAGCCCUUCCCUGCACCCCCAGAGGACGACGCAGCCACAGCAAAGGAGGCAGCAAAGCCCAGCCCUGCCAUGGAUGUGCAGUUCCCGGUGCCAAAUCUGGAGGUCCUGCCCCGGCCCCCAGUGGUUGCUUCCACACCUGCACCCAAGGCUGAGCCUGCCAUCAUCCCUGCCACCCGGAACGAGCCCAUCGGGCUGAAGGCCUCCGACUUCCUGCCCGCCGUGAAGAUCCCCCAGCAGGCCGAGCUGGUGGACGAGGAUGCCAUGUCACAGAUCCGCAAAGGCCACGACACCAUGUGUGUGGUGCUCACCAGCCGCCACAAGAACCUGGACACUGUGCGGGCUGUGUGGACCAUGGGCGACAUCAAGACGUCGGUGGACUCCGCUGUGGCCAUCAACGACCUGUCGGUGGUGGUGGACCUCCUGAACAUCGUCAACCAGAAAGCCUCCCUGUGGAAGCUGGACCUGUGCACCACCGUCCUGCCACAGAUUGAGAAGCUUCUGCAGAGCAAGUAUGAGAGCUACGUCCAGACGGGCUGCACCUCCCUGAAGCUGAUCCUGCAGCGGUUUCUGCCCCUCAUCACAGACAUGCUGGCGGCCCCACCCUCUGUGGGUGUGGAUAUCAGCAGGGAGGAGAGGCUGCAUAAGUGCCGGCUCUGCUACAAGCAGCUUAAGAGCAUCAGCGGCCUGGUCAAGAGCAAGUCAGGCCUGAGCGGCCGCCAUGGCAGUACCUUCCGCGAGCUGCACCUGCUCAUGGCCAGUCUGGACUGAGGAAAGCAGUGGGCAGGGGCGCUCGGCAGCCCACAGGGCCUGGCCUCAGCCCCCACUCCUGUUCCUUGUGCACCCACUGGCCCAUGAGCCUCUGCCUGGCCCCUGCUGCUGUCCUGUGGCCGUCCUGGAGGAGGUGAUGCUGGUCCCUGGCCACCUCUACAGCCCUGAACUCUUGAGACAACUCUCUCCAGCAAUAGCUGCCCAGCUUUGCCCAACUGUUGCUUCUUGGGGCAGCGAACUGAGCCCUGGGGCUGCUGCUGUAAUUUAUAAGGCAAAUUUUAUUAAAUUUGUAACUAUU